AAGCGGUGGCUCCACUGGAGGAAAACACACCCCGGUCUCACAUUAAAGAAGCCAAACUGUCGGCUUCAAAGAGAAAAGGCAACAUCCUGUCACAGGCCAUGCUCUGGCAAAAACUGGUAUAGAAAGGCAAUAUGGUGAACUUCUCAGCCCGAAAAAGGAGAUCUCCAAUCAGGGCCGAGAGGCUCAUGCUAAGGUGGAAAGAUUUUCCUCCGUGAUGGACUCUUGGAUACCUACGGGAGACUUAAAAGGCCCUCAGACCACAGGAUUAAUGGUUGGUGUGAAAGGUACCAACUGCAAGUUUCAACUUGCAAAAACACUUGGCCGUUGGGCUCCUUUGGAAUCGUCUUGAAGCUUCAGAUUCUGAUAUUUCAUGAGCACUUUGCAAAGUCACUAUGAGAAGCACCCUCCUUCUUACCUGCUCAGCUGGAGUCAGUUACAGAAUUCCUUGGCAGCUGGCUGUGGACACGUGCCGGGCAGUCAGGAGACCCGUGGGAGCUGUGGGAGUCCUGCAACGUCAAUAGGAAGAGCCACAGCUCCGGAGCAAGCCCCAGCCCCGGCCCGGCCAUACCAGGGCGUCCGUGUGAAGGAGCCAGUGAAGGAACUGCUGAGGAGGAAGCGAGGCCACGCCAGCAGUGGGGCAGCACCUGCACCUACGGCGGUGGUGCUGCCCCAUCAGCCCCUGGCGACCUACACCACAGUGGGUCCUUCCUGCCUGGACAUGGAAGGUUCUGUGUCUGCAGUGACAGAGGAGGCUGCCCUGUGUGCCGGCUGGCUCUCCCAGCCCACCCCGGCCACCCUGCAGCCCCUGGCCCCAUGGACACCUUACACCGAGUAUGUGCCCCAUGAAGCUGUCAGCUGCCCCUACUCAGCUGACAUGUAUGUGCAGCCCGUGUGCCCCAGCUACACGGUGGUGGGGCCCUCCUCAGUGUUGACCUAUGCCUCUCCGCCACUCAUCACCAAUGUCACGGGUCCAGUGUCAUCCUGAUGCACCUGCCCCUGCCUCCAAGCACCUUCUAUGAAAGGCCUGCAGAAGCCCUUCCCUCCCAGGUCCACCUGCCUACCCAGCAAACCAAUUUUGGAGCCUGGAUGAUGAUAGAUAAGAAGGAGUUAAUCCAACACCUCUCCCAGGCAACUCAUUUCCAUGUCAGAGGCCUGGGGUGAGGGUGGUGGGUGGAGGACUCACGGCUCCCACCCAUUUCAUUACCAAGGAUUCCUUUCAUUAUUUAUCCCCUUUCAUCAUUCCCACCUUCUGCUUUGAAAGGUUCUGUAUAUCAAACAAACAGUAUUCAUUAAGAAUUGAUUUAUUUGUUUUGCCAUUUUGUAAAUUAAGUCAUCAAAGCUGGCUAGAGCUGUAAGUCCACACUCCUGAUCAGCAGAGAUAAGACCUGCUGUGUGCUGAGUGGAAGUAAUUGUAUUCCCGAGCAAAGAAACCUAUAGUUACAGGUUUAUGACUGGGAAAUGUAGAAUUUCCAUCUGGAUUUUUGAAAAGCUGGGAAUCAUGAGGCUUUCCCGGAUUCUGUCUGGUUUCAGGACACUGGGAUGGGGACCACUGGCUUAAGUCAAAGGAGAGGAAGUGAUUAUGCUGUGGUGGGGUGUACACCUCAGCCCGGAUUUCAGGAGGCUGGAAGGCCUCUGAGACCAUUUCCAGCUCUAUCAUUCUGUGCAAAAACACCCUAAAGCCUUGCUACUCAAACUCUUGUCCCUGGACUGGCCACAUUGGAGUCCCCCUGAGAUCUGAUUAGACAUGCAAAAUCCCAGGCCCCACUCUAGACUUCCUGUGCCAGAAGCUGCGUUCUAACAAGAUCCCCAGGAGGUUGAGAAAAGCCCUGCCCUAAAUGAUUCUAACAGUUUGCUGUCAAGACACAGUGACAGUAGGAGGGAUAUAUGACAGGGGAGACAGGGAUGGUAGGGGGAGAUUUUGGCCUCCCUCUCAUGAAUCCAUGCAGAGAGCAUCCUCUUCUAUCUGCUUUCCUCAAGUGUGAAAGAAAAGUAAGAAUCCAGGUCCCGCCCCUGUUGCAGGCCUGAUCUGAGGUUUGUGAGGGCAGUCGCCGUGCAGGUGAGAGGUAUGACUCGCAGAGCAUUCAGGAGAAGGACUCUAACACUUGGAGGGUCAUGGGGGGUGCCCAUAAGUGGGAUGGCCAUGGAGAUCAGCUCAGAGACAGAGGACGAUGAGGAUGUGGAAGGCACCAGGCAGCAGCAGGAAGGAAGGCCAAGUUUGCUGACAAAGCAGUGCUUCCCCCAUCUGGGGAUGGCCAGGCCUCCCCAUGCUGGCCACCACUAGAGGGGUGGGAGGUGAUGGAGCUGUGUUGGCCCAAGGGGACCUCCAAAGCUGUUGUGUGGAGCCCGGACUGUCUUUGUGUCUGGGCAGGACAGUGGCCACCUUCCAGAUACAGCUUCCAGGCUGUGGUUUAACAUAUAUUUUCACAGAUUUUAAGAUGCAUAUAUUUUUAAUGUUUUAAGAUCUCUGAAAUAGAAAUGAAUUUUGUAUUCAACGAAACCUGGAAAAUCCUCUCUAAUUGGCCUAACCCAAUGAGUUCAUUACUGUUUGUAUUCUAUUUCGUAGAUGAGAAAAAUGAGCCUUCUGAGCAGGAAGUGGCCUGAGCAAAGACAUAUAGCUAGGAAGGGUCAGGAUUGGGGCUGCGGUUGAAGUCAGCCUGGCUCCUCCCUUGGGGAAGACUUUGAGCAGGAGGAGGUGGAGCCCCAUGAAGUGAGAAACCAGGAAAGGGCAGAAUUGAAGGGGGAGAUGGAGACCCCUCUAAGGGCAAGGAUGGGUGGAUGGGUCUCCUGGGGCUGCUAACCCUCUGUCACGUGUUUUCCUGUCACAGACAAGAAGCUCCGCCACGCCCGCAGUGGGGCCCCCGCUGGAGGGCCCAGAGCACCAGGCACCCCUCACCUAUUUCCCGUGGCCUCAGCCCCUUUCCACACUACCCACCUCCACCCUGCAGUACCAGCCUCCGGCCCCAGCCCUACCUGGGCCCCAGUUUGUCCAGCUCCCCAUCUCUAUCCCAGAGCCAGUCCUUCAGGACAUGGAAGACCCCAGAAGAGCCGCCAGCUCGUUGACCAUCGACAAGCUGCUUUUGGAGGAAGAGGAUAGCGACGCCUAUGCGCUUAACCACACUCUCUCUGUGGAAGGCUUUUAGGCGUGGCUCCCACCUGAGUCCUGUUCCCUGAAACUGGGAUUUUAAAAUGAGCCUGGAAUUGAGCCCCAGGUUCAUGCUUGUUUGGAGUAGUCAUUUCAUGACUACACUUUCUACGCACAGCUAGAAUUGUAGACCUGUAAACCUUCCUUCCCUUCUUCCUUCCCCUCCCUCCCUCACUUCCUCCCUCUCCCCCAUCCUUCCAUUCUUCCCCUCCCUCCCUUCUUCCUUUCCAACCCCUUCCUUCCUUUUCCUCCCUCCCUUCCUUCCCUCCUUCCCUUCUCCCUUUCCAACCCCUUCCUUCCUUUUCCUCCCUCCCUUCCUUCCCUCCUUCCCUUCUCCCUUUCCUUCUUUACCUCCCUCCCUCCCUCGCUUCUUCUCUCUUUCUUACUUCUUUUUUCAAUUCUGUUCCAUUUUGGGAGGUAAUUAUAGGGAUUUUAGCAAUAACAUUUUAUGUCAAAUGUUGCCAAGUCUGUGGUCCAUGGGCUUUCAUUUCUGUCACAUUUCAUUUCUUGGAAAAGGCCUCCUUCCUCCAGUGCCUGCUGAACCAUCUUAGGGUCACUCACACCCUCUGUAAUUUUAAGAUGUAUGUGGUGGCCGGCGGGAAGACCAGCCCCGACAGCACCUCCUGAGAAAGUCAGCCAAGGGCCUACCCUGAUGCCAGAGUCCUUGAGCUGUCAGUUCCCACAGUUGCUCCUUUGUUUGCUCUUCUCAGCCUCGGCCAGAUUUACAGUCCAGGCAGCAAAAUCUCAAGGCCUGGGGCUCAGAGUAGUAAGGGGUGGGAAGUGGGUGGCAGGGAGAAAAGAACAUCAGGGUGGGUGGGGACAGGCCAGUGACGAAGAGAGGGACAGAGGAGGGAUGGGAACAGGCUGUGCAUCUUAGUUGGAGAGAGGGGUGUGGGAGGAAGCUUGAGUUUGAUGCAGGGAGGAGGAAGGCUGAGGAAUGACUUGGCUCCAGAUUACUUGGUUAUUAAGAAGAACAAUAAACUAAAGGAAAGCAUUGCUUGAAGAGAUGGUUUUGCUGCUCUCCUUGAGGAUACGUGCAAGGGAAGUUGGGCUGUUGUAAACAGGGUGAAGGGUGUGUUUGGUCGGCCAUUUCUGUCUCACCUCUAGGCCCUCUGCUGGUGCUGUGGAGGCCAAGACCCCAUUAAGCCUAAAGGUGAUGGGUCCUCGCCUAGGCUUAGUGCUACCAUGUGGGUUUUGUUUCUUUCCUUCCUUCCUUCCUUCCUUCCUUCCUUCCUUCCUUCCUUCCUUCCUUCCUUCCUUCCUUCUUUCCUUCCUUCCUUCCUUCCUUCCUUCCUCUCUCUUUCUUUCUUUUUUUUGGUUUUUUUUGGGACGGAGUCUCACUCCAUUGCCCAGGCUGGAGUACAAUGGUGCGAUCUUGGCUCACUGCACCUCUGUCUCCCAAGUUCAAGUGAUUCUCCUGCCUGAGCCUCCCGAGUAGCUGGGAUUACAGGUGCAUGCCACCAUGCCUGGCUAAUUUUUGUAUUUUUAGUAGAGACGGGGUUUCACCAUGUUGGCCAGGCUGGUCUCGAACUCCUGACCUUGUGAUCCGCCCGCCUCAGCCUCUCAGAGUGCUGGGAUCACAGGCGUGAGCCACCGCACCCAGCCUUUUACCAUGUGGGUUUCUUUAGUGUCUUAAAAGCGUCCAUAAGCCACCAUUCUGUGGAACCAAGGCCCCCUCCACGCAAACACCCUCCCUCCUGGGGACCUCUGGAGCCUCAGCCAGAAGUACCAUUAGGUUUAAUUUUAAUUUGUUUUGCUGGAGAAACAUCAGGUUUGUAGGAGACUGAGUUGUUAGCAGGUGUGCUUAGCUCUUGAUAGUGAACGUGUACCUUGGGAACUGGCUCACCCACCUGCUAAUAGCACCAUCGUCACUAUUAAGCAGACAUUUCAGUUGGUAGAAUCCAUGUAGAAGUCAUGGACUUUUCUGGGAAAUGACUUUUCUGGGAAAUGACAGUUUCUUUGACAUAUUUUCUUUGCCCACUUUAAAUAAAAACUCUGGAGAAA